AUAAAUCUAGAGACUCCAGGAUUUUAACGUUCUGCUGGACUGAGCUGGUUGCCUCAUGUUAUUAUGCAGGCAACUCACUUUAUCCCAAUUUCUUGAUACUUUUCCUUCUGGAGGUCCUAUUUCUCUAACAUCUUCCAGAAAAGUCUUAAAGCUGCCUUAACCUUUUUUCCAGUCCACCUCUUAAAUUUUUUCCUCCUCUUCCUCUAUACUAACAUGAGUGUGGAUCCAGCUUGUCCCCAAAGCUUGCCUUGCUUUGAAGCAUCCGACUGUAAAGAAUCUUCACCUAUGCCUGUGAUUUGUGGGCCUGAAGAAAACUAUCCAUCCUUGCAAAUGUCUUCUGCUGAGAUGCCUCACACGGAGACUGUCUCUCCUCUUCCUUCCUCCAUGGAUCUGCUUAUUCAGGACAGCCCUGAUUCUUCCACCAGUCCCAAAGGCAAACAACCCACUUCUGCAGAGAAGAGUGUCGCAAAAAAGGAAGACAAGGUCCCGGUCAAGAAACAGAAGACCAGAACUGUGUUCUCUUCCACCCAGCUGUGUGUACUCAAUGAUAGAUUUCAGAGACAGAAAUACCUCAGCCUCCAGCAGAUGCAAGAACUCUCCAACAUCCUGAACCUCAGCUACAAACAGGUGAAGACCUGGUUCCAGAACCAGAGAAUGAAAUCUAAGAGGUGGCAGAAAAACAACUGGCCGAAGAAUAGCAAUGGUGUGACGCAGAAGGCCUCAGCACCUACCUACCCCAGCCUUUACUCUUCCUACCACCAGGGAUGCCUGGUGAACCCGACUGGGAACCUUCCAAUGUGGAGCAACCAGACCUGGAACAAUUCAACCUGGAGCAACCAGACCCAGAACAUCCAGUCCUGGAGCAACCACUCCUGGAACACUCAGACCUGGUGCACCCAAUCCUGGAACAAUCAGGCCUGGAACAGUCCCUUCUAUAACUGUGGAGAGGAAUCUCUGCAGUCCUGCAUGCAGUUCCAGCCAAAUUCUCCUGCCAGUGACUUGGAGGCUGCCUUGGAAGCUGCUGGGGAAGGCCUUAAUGUAAUACAGCAGACCACUAGGUAUUUUAGUACUCCACAAACCAUGGAUUUAUUCCUAAACUACUCCAUGAACAUGCAACCUGAAGACGUGUGAAGAUGAGUGAAACUGAUAUUACUCAAUUUCAGUCUGGACACUGGCUGAAUCCUUCCUCUCCCCUCCUCCCAUCCCUCAUAGGAUUUUUCUUGUUUGGAAACCACGUGUUCUGGUUUCCAUGAUGCCCAUCCAGUCAAUCUCAUGGAGGGUGGAGUAUGGUUGGAGCCUAAUCAGCGAGGUUUCUUUUUUUUUUUUUUUCCUAUUGGAUCUUCCUGGAGAAAAUACUUUUUUUUUUUUUUUUUUUGAAACGGAGUCUUGCUCUGUCGCCCAGGCUGGAGUGCAGUGGCGCGGUCUUGGCUCACUGCAAGCUCCGUCUCCCGGGUUCACGCCAUUCUCCUGCCUCAGCCUCCCGAGCAGCUGGGACUACAGGCGCCCGCCACCUCGCCCGGCUAAUAUUUUGUAUUUUUAGUAGAGACGGGGUUUCACUGUGUUAGCCAGGAUGGUCUCGAUCUCCUGACCUUGUGAUCCACCCGCCUCGGCCUCCCUAACAGCUGGGAUUUACAGGCGUGAGCCACCGCGCCCUGCCUAGAAAAGACAUUUUAAUAACCUUGGCUGCCGUCUCUGGCUAUAGAUAAGUAGAUCUAAUACUAGUUUGGAUAUCUUUAGGGUUUAGAAUCUAACCUCAAGAAUAAGAAAUACAAGUACAAAUUGGUGAUGAAGAUGUAUUCGUAUUGUUUGGGAUUGGGAGGCUUUGCUUAUUUUUUAAAAACUAUUGAGGUAAAGGGUUAAGCUGUAACAUACUUAAUUGAUUUCUUACCGUUUUUGGCUCUGUUUUGCUAUAUCCCCUAAUUUGUUGGUUGUGCUAAUCUUUGUAGAAAGAGGUCUCGUAUUUGCUGCAUCGUAAUGACAUGAGUACUGCUUUAGUUGGUUUAAGUUCAAAUGAAUGAAACAACUAUUUUUCCUUUAGUUGAUUUUACCCUGAUUUCACCGAGUGUUUCAAUGAGUAAAUAUACAGCUUAAACAUAAAUCUUUGUUAAAUUUUUGGUUGGGGUGGAGAAGGAAAUUAGCUGAGGACACUGCUAUCUUAGAAAUGCAUAGAAAUAGCUGAGCGUGGUGGCCUAUGCCUGUAGUCCCAGCUAUUUGGGAGGCUGAGGCAGGAGAAUCGCUUGAACCUGGUAGGUGGAGGUUGUAGUGAGCCAAUAUCACACCACUGCACUCCAGCUUGGGCGACAAGAGCAAAACUCCCAUCUCAAAAAUAAAUAAAUAAAUAAGUAAAUAAAUGAAUAAUAAAUAAAUAUGCCAGUUUUAGAAUGAAUGAAUAAUAAAUAUGCCAGUUUUAGAAAAAAGGGCACUUACGUGCAUUGUACAUGUGCAUCUACAAAUGUAAUGGGUUAUUUCCGUGUAUGAAUCUGUAAUUGAUGCUAACAUUUAAAGUUUCAUCAGAGGCCUAUAUGUAAGUAAAUUCUAAGGCUAGUUGAAACAGAUUUAUGUUCUCACCUUAAGAGCAGCUACGCAGGCAUCUGUGAAUUAUACUAAUAAUCCUUUACUGUCCUUUUCCCAUCUUGUGCCUGCCCUAAAUGUAUCUGAUCUGAGAGCACGUCCCUUCACUCUGAAGCAGCAUGAUGCAGGUUAUCAGAGUGGUUUUUUCCAGUCUUUUCUCUCAUUAUUUCCCCAAUUGUCCAAUGUUACUAAGACUAUCCAGUCUAAUUCCAAGUGUUUUUUUUUUGUUUUAUUUUGUUUUUUUUUAAGACUGGAGUCUUACUCUGUUGCCCAGGCUGGAGUGUAGUGGAGCGAUCUCGGCUCACCGCAACCUCCGCCUCCCGAGUUCAAGUGAUUCUCCUGCCUCAGCCUCCCAAGUAGCUGGGACUACAGGGGUGAGCCACCAUGCCCAGCUAAUUGUAUUUUUAGUAGAGACAGGGUUUCACUAUGUUGGCCAGGCUGGUCUUGAACUCCUGACCUCAUGAUCCACCAGCCUUGGCCUCCCAAAGUGUUGGGAUUACAGGCGUGAGCCACUGCGCCUGGCCUAUCGUUUGUUUUUUUAGACAGUCUCUCUCUAUUGCCCAGGCUGGAGUGCAGUGGCACAAUCUUGGCUCACUGCAACCUCCGCCUCCUGGGUUCGAGCAAUUCUCCUGCGUCAGCCUCCUAAGUAGCUGGGAUUACAGGCACCCAACAUUACACCCGGCUAAUUUUUGGUAUUUUUAGUAGAGAUGGGGUUUCACCAUGUUGGCCAGCCUGGUCUCGAACUCCUGACCUCAGGUGAUCCACCUGACUCGGCCUCCCAAAGUGGUGGGAUUAUAGGUGUGAGCCACCGUGUCUGGGCAAUUUUUUUUUUUUUUUUUGAGAUGGAACUUCACUUUUGUUACUCAGGCUGGAGCACAAUGAUGCAAUCUCUACUCACUGCAACCUGCACCUCCCAGGUUCAAGUGAUUCUCUUGCCUCAGCCUUUCGAGUGGCUGGUAUUACAGGGAUUUGCCACUAUGCCCAGCUAAUUCUUUGUAUUUAGUAGAGAUGGGGUUUCACCGUAUUGACCAGGCUGGUCUCGAACUCCUGACCUCAGGUAAUCCACCCUCCUCGGUCUCCCAAAGUGCUAGGAUUACAGGCAUGAGCCACAGUGCCCAGCCUUCUUUUUUAUUUUUUUAAGACGGGCUUAUUCUGCUGCUCAGACUGGGGCUUAGUGGCACCAUUUCACCUCACUGUAGCCUCGACUUCCCGGAUUCAAGCAAUCCUCCUGCCUGAGUCUCUCAAAUAGCCCAGACUAUAGGUGCACACCACCAUGCCAGCUAACUUUUGUGUUUUUAGGAGAGACGGGGUUUCCCCAUGUUGGCCUGGCUAGUCUCAAACUCCUGAGCUCAAGCAGUCUACCAGCCUUGGCCUCCCGAAGUGCUGAGAUUACAGGCAUGAGUCACCAGCCUAGCCCUGUAUUAUGUUUUCUGAACUUUUUUUUUUUUAAUCACCCAGUAUUAAUCUUCAACCUCUUGGCAGGUAAGAAUUUAGAGAUCUAUUUGGAAUAAUCUUUAAAGUAACAAUAAUAACUACAGUCAAAAGCAGUAAGAUUAGUGGGCCAGGUGCCGUGGCUCACACCUGUAAUCCCAGCACUUCGGGAGACCAAGGCAGGUGGAUCACCUGAGGUCAGGAGUUCAAGUUUAGCAUGGCCAAUAUGGCGAAACCCUGUCUCUACUAAAAAUACAGAAAUUUGCCAGAGGUCUUGGUUUGCGCCUGUAAUCUCAGCUACUUGGAAGGCGGAGGCAGGAUAAUCACUUGAACCCGGGAGGUUGCAGUGACCCCAGAUAAUGCCACCCCACUCCAGCCUGGGCGACAGAGCGUCACUGUCUCAAAAAUAAACAAAAAUAAUAGGAGAUUAGGCAAAAAGGAUAGUACAAGGCUCUCUGUUUAACAUUUCUUCCUUUCUCUAGAAAAUUUUCCUUUCUUUUCCCAAAAGGAGGUGUGUGUUACUUCCAAUGCUAUAUUUUAGUAGCUUUACCAUAUUUUAGUUUUUAAAAUUCAUUAUUUUGAUUUCUCAGCUUUCAUUUUCAUUUCAGUUUGUACCUGAAGGAGAGAAGCAUGGAUUGAAUUUGCCUGGGUUUUCCGAAUUUCAUAAUAUAAAUUUAAAACUCAGAAGUGGGAGGAAUACAGGCCUUGAUUAGUGAAUUUCAAGCUCAGUUCUCGGGGUGAAGGACAAGGUUAAUUCUACUCUGAGUAAUUCUACCGUUCAGAAAACCUGGUGUGUCUACAGGAAAAAAUACAGGCUGUGACUACAAACCUAAAAGUAAAGGCAAACAACUGCCAGACAGAGGCAGGAAAGUGGGGGAGAGCCCUUGGUAAAUAUUGCAUGCCUCCUGGGGCCCCCAUGGGCUUUGACUCAAGGGGGAGAUGAAGGGAAUUUGUUAAAGAAAGAAGUCACUGGGACAGACAAAAGCUUCCGGCACAGGAAGUUAGUUCGACUAAGGAUACCGAAAUGUAGGAAUUUGAAUGGGUUCCUGGGUGUGAGGUUGAAGUGAAACUUGAUUGAAAAGAAGCUGCUGGUGGUGAGUCUCUCCUUAAGCUAUUCCUGGCUUCUGGGUAGUUGGUGUAAACUCUGUGGUCCUUGAAUAAAGUGUGCUUGAGAAUUUUA